CUCUGUGGAUUCUGGCCAGGCCGGGUUCGGCGGUUGCUGUGAGAGCGGGCUUCCCAACACCAUGCCGUCCGCCUUCUCUGUCAGCUCUUUCCCCGUCAGCAUCCCAGCCGUGCUCACGGUACAGCAGGGUCCCGGGGAGUCCAGGAGGCGGCGGAGUGCGGCACUGUCUGGAGAGUUCAGUGUAUUGCAGAGAGGUUGGAGAAAAUCAAGUCUUGCACGUGGCGAUGGCUCAAGAUUCCCUGAGGUCUUCAGUGCUGACUAAGGAGUCUGAAAUGAUGAUUCAUGUUUUACCUUUGGGGCUGAGCCAAGUGCAUCUCUUUGAGCAAUCGUCUUAAUUUCCUUGUCGUCACCAAUUAUCAUAACCAAUUAUCAUCGUAAAGGAUGGUAAUUCCUUUAAUUAUACCCACCUUAAAAACAUGAUUCUGUUCCACAAACGAAAGGAGCACAUCAGAGAUGCCUUCAGUUCUGUGUGCUUGAACUUUGAAUUCCAUGAAUUAUAGUUGCACUGAGGGGAGAAUCCUGUUUCCAUCCUCCUGGUUCCUUCUCCCUUUCCUGUCCCCAUGUUUCUCUGAGGCCUGGCAAUGCUCUCUGGAUACUUGCAGACGGACUGGACUGAGCCCUGGCUCAUGGGGCUGGCCACCUUCCACGCGCUCUGCGUGCUCCUCACCUGCUUGUCCUCCCGAAGCUACAGACUACAGAUCGGGCACUUUCUGUGUCUAGUCAUCUUAGUCUACUGUGCUGAAUACAUCAAUGAGGCGGCUGCGAUGAACUGGAGAUUAUUUUCGAAAUACCAGUAUUUCGACUCCAGGGGGAUGUUCAUUUCUAUAGUAUUUUCAGCCCCACUGCUGGUGAAUGCCAUGAUCAUUGUGGUUAUGUGGGUAUGGAAGACUUUGAAUGUGAUGACUGACCUGAAGAAUGCACAAGAGAGAAGAAAGGAAAAGAAAAGGAGAAGGAAAGAAGACUGAGGGGCAGCAGCUGCUUGGAGUUUGCGUCCUUCCCGUCCACCCAGUGCAGCUCCCAGUGCUGCAGUGUGCGUGGCGUGGGCAUCCUUCCAGCUGACUCAUGGUUUGAAAAACCGUUGUUUUAUUUAAAUAUCCACAGUGGUAGGGCACACACUGAAGUUGGCUUUUCAGCCAGCACUGAAUGUAUCCAUCAGGACAUGCGUCUUCAGGUGCCUGAUCUUUGUAGUCAGGCUGUGGGAACGGUCUCUGCAGAGCUUCAUAACUGGGAAUUUGAUUUGAAGAAGUCCAUGUCAUAUGUGUAACUAGUACUAAUUAUAAAUAUAAAAUACACAAUAUAAAAUAUGAAACUCAAUAAUAAACAGUGCCACCUGUACAUGGGCACCAUGCCCUCCUCCUCGUGCUGUGUUUUCUAGUGCAUGCCACAGUUCGCAGUAGAGGGUGUUUUCACCUUCCAAGACAUGGGGCAAAGUUUGGAGACACCUGGUUGUCACUGGAGGGGGUGGUGCUCCUGGCUUCUCCUGUGGAGCCCGGGGUGAUGCAUAAAAUCCUGUGUGCCUGGGUCAGCCGCAUCACAGACAAUGACUUGACAUGAAAUGUCAGCUGUGCUGGGGCAGAGAGACCUUGGAAGGAAGCUCUUGGAAAAUACGUUGUAUCUCAGUUUGAUGAACCAAUUCACAAGAGGCUAGGCCCUCUCUAGCAAAGUUAUGGGCUGCUUUACUGAAAACAGAAUGGAAGCCCUGAAGUCAACACUCCAUGGAGAAGCGUGUCUUUCCUAAUGUCCUGGUGUUCUGUUGAUUUAGGUGCUUGGGAACACAAUGCUCCCAGUUCUGUUAGGACAGGCAUACUGUUACUUUGCAAUAUCCACUUUAUAAAAUAGCUCCUGCCCAGUGGCUCUUGGUUCCUGUCAAAUGUGGACCUGUAGUUUAAGAAUGACAGGUGGUUAGAGACCCAGAUAUUUAAAAAUAGGUGUUCAAUAAGGGAAUACUGAUUGUGCAUUGUAUCUGGAUAGCAUGCCUAAUUGUGCAUUUCUGAAAGUUACCAAUUCAAAAUGUAAUUGGAACAGUUAUCUUUGAUUAGACAAGCCUGGGAAGAGAAUGUUGAGGUGCAGAGCUCACCAGCCAAGUUCAUGCCCCUCUCGGGCCUUUGUGGCUGAGAAGUGGGACAGAAAGAUGAUUAAGGUAAUGUGUCCUCCCUGUAGCAUUGUCCAGGGCCGUUGUGUAGAUAUUUGACUUCACUGACAGAAAAGAAACCAGGGAGUUUGUAGAGACUGUGCAUUUUUAGUAUAACAUUUUCACCAUCUGAUAUGGUUUGGCUUUGUGUCCCCACCCAAAUUGCAUCUCAAAUUGUAAUCCCCAUGUGUCAAGGGAGGGACCUGAUGGGAGGUGAUGGGAUCAUGGGGGUGGUUUCCCCUAUGUUGUUAUCAUAAUAGAGAGGGAGUUCUCACAAGAUCUGCUGGUUUUAAAGACAGCAGUUUCCCCUGCUGUCACUGUCUCUCUCCUGCUGCCUUGUGAAGAAGGUGCUUGUUUCUCCCUCUGCCAUGAUUGUAAGUUUCCCGAGGCCUCCCCGGCCAUGUGGAACUGAGUCAAUUAAACUUCUUGUUUAUAAAGUAAUCCAGGUCUCAGGUAGUAUCUUUAUAGCAGUGUGAGAACAGACUAAUUAAACAUCUAUAUGUUAUUUGGACUUAAUAUGGGGCCGUGUGAUUGAAUCUCAGUUUGCCUGUGAUAAAGUAGUGUAACAGUAUUGCUAGCUUUGCAUGAAUUUGAUGCUGAUGACAUGUCAGUGUGAAACCAUGACGUGUGGUCUUUGAUUUUCAUUCUGCAUGUGUGUGUCUGUGUUUUGGAACAGUUAUAUUUUGGUUUUGUAAAAACAACCUUCACUUUAUUUUUAACUGUGUAGUAAGUUUAUAUUCAAUGCCUUAAAGUGCAUUGUUAACAAUUGUCUUGAUAUGUUGUCCUCAUUUUAGGGAAAGUCAUAGAAGCCAAAAUGAUCAGCAGUUGAGUAAUUUACGAAAGCACAGGUGCAAUCCCACUUUAAAGCACUGGGGGUUGCACAGAGCACACUGGUUUCAGGCUCCAUAAAUGUGGAUGACUCACUGGAGAGCUUCAUCUGUUUAAGUAGAACAAAUGUUUUUACUCUACUGAUAAAGUACAGGAAAGGAGGUUUGGGAUCAAAAUUAUUUUUCACAUUCCAAACCUGUGACACCUUACGUUUAUCGAUUGCUAUGCAAUAAAAUACAUCUUUAAUAAUAUGUAGUAUUUUUUUUUGUUUUUUUCAAAAAAAUGGUAUUUGUUUUGCACCUUACUGUAACUGGAAACAGGAGCACCUGGAACUUAGCUCCACCUUUGGCUGGCAGGUCCCUUUGCUGCAGCAUCUGGUGCUGAGUUUUAACAAACAAAUGCAAUUGUGUCCUUGCCAGUAGAAGAAAGUCUACUUGCACAGAUAAUGUAUAUCAAAUCAGAAAGCAAUAUGCAACCUGAAUGGCUAGCUUCUGUGAGAAGUAAAGUGGCAAGGAAAUGUUAACAUGUUCUUGCCCUUUACAAAAUAAUAAAUGUUAAAAAAAAAAAAAAAGGGCUGGGGGUGGAAUUCAGGGUAAGGAGCUUCAGUGGCGCGAAGUUGAGUGGGAUGCUUAAAGACAGACGAGAAUUGCCGUCAGAGAUAUACCGGUCAGGCCCAAGCAUCUUUUCCCUGGAAAAGAACUUCAGGCUUCCUUGUCUGGAUUUCAGUGGAGCACCCUUCUUCUUUCACCAAGUUAACCAGAACAUGUUUUCAGUGCAGCCUUCCCCUCUUUACUGAAGCCCCUCUUGCUGGUCGACUACACCAGCAAGUCGGUCCUGGGGAGGACGGGGCUGGGCUCCACAUGCAGAGUUCUCGGAGGCAGGAAGGGAGCGAGCCAGGGCAGAGAAGAGCACCCAGGGGGUGGCGCUGCCCAGUCCCAGGAUGGUGCGAAGAUGUCUCCAAGCCCUGGUUGCUGCACAGGGAAGGCAGGAUGGGGCGGCGAGGCCCACGCAGGCUGUGGGUGCCAUGCGUUGGUGGCAGCUUGUUCCGAGUGGGGCUGGAACAGUUGACAGCAAGCAUCCUCAUCGGCCUGGUAAGCUUUCUAGCUCCUCUUCCUCCGAUGUUCCAGUUUCACAGCGGCCUGUACAGUUAGAUCUUUCCUCGCUUUGGGGGAAGGUGUAGCUAUUAUAGUCUCCGAAUCAUGCUGUCAUUAGAAAUUGCACAAGACCUAUGCCAGGGGAGGCGCUGACUGGCACAGGCCCUGAAAGGAACCUGAGGACAGAGAAGGAGCUCCCUGCAGCCUUCAGGCAGCCAAGCAGAGGCCUAAGUCCAAGCAUGUGGCCAUAGGGUCUGCUCUGUAAGCCUCAGGGCUACUGCCUUCUGCUCCAGUCCUGGGCCAAAACACCCUUCAGCAGCUCCUGCUCCAUCUGAGCGAGCUGGAUGUCAGCCUCCAUGGGCCCUGUUGUGCAUGGGGUUGAUGCUUCAUCUGAGUGAGCUGGGCAUCUGCCUCCAUGGGUCCUGUUGUGUGUAGGGUUGAUGCUCCAUCUCAGUGAGCUGAGCAUCUGCAUCUCGGGGUUCUGUUGUACAUGGGGUUAAUACUCCAUCCGAGUGAGCUGGGCAUCCGCAUCUCUGGGUUUUGUGUGCGUGGGGUUAACACUCCAUCUGAGUGAGCUGGGUGACUGCCUCCAUGAGUCCUGUUGUGUGUGGGGUUGAUGCUCCAUCUGAGUGAGUGGGGCAUCUGCAUCUCUGUGUCCUGUUGUGUGUGGGGUUGAUGCUGCAUCUGAGUGAGUGGGGCAUCUGCAUCUCUGGGUCCUGUUGUGUGUGGGGUUGAUGCUCCAUCUGAGUGAGUGGGGCAUCUGCAUCUCUGGGUCCUGUUGUAUGUAGGGUUGAUUCUCUAUCUGAGUGAGUGGGGCAUCUGCAUCUCUGGGUUCUGUUGUAUGUGGGGUUGUUGCUCUGAGUGAGUGGUGCAUCUGCAUCUCUGGGUUCUAUUUUAUGUGGGGUUGAUUCUCUGAGUGAGUGGGGCAUCUGCAUCUCUGGGUUCUAGUUUAUGUGGGGUUGAUUCUCUGUCUGAGUGAGUGGGGUGUUUGCAUCUCUGGGUCCUGUUGUAUGUGGAGUUGAUUCUCUAUCUGAGUGAGUGGAGCAUCUGCAUCUCUGGGUCCUGUUGUAUGUGGGGUUGAUUAUCUGAGUGAAUGGGGCAUCUGCAUCUCUGGGUUCUAGUUUAUGUGGGGUUGAUUCUCUAUCUGAGUGAGUGGUGCAUCUGCAUCUCUGGGUUCUAUUUUAUGUGGGGUUGAUUCUCUAUCUGAGUGAGUGGGGUGUCUGCAUCUCUGGAUCCUGUUGUAUAUGGGGUUGAUUCUCUAUCGGAGUGAGUGGGGCAUCUGCAUCUCUGGGUUCUGUUGUAUGUGGGAGUGAUGCUCCAUCUGAGCUGGGCGUCUGCAUCUCUGGGUUUAUGGAUCCCUAAGCCCAACUCACUCACAGCUUGGCCCUCCAUGUGCUGGUCUUUCCUCUGCCUUACCCAUGUUUGGUUAUUUCUUAUAUAACAUUGGAUAUCUUUGGAACAGGAGAAAAUUGUUAAGUGUCAAUUUGCUGCCCCUUUUUUCUGUAAGUCUAUCUUCUAUAAAGUAAUGUAGUCCCUAUUAUCAUGAUGCUAUUUCACUAUAUAACAUUAUUUUCAAUGCCUGCAUAGUAAACACAUUGUAGGGGUAUAGGCUGAAUUUACGUAACCAGUUACUGAUAUUAGAGAUGCAGAGUUUUUCUAAUUGUUUUACUGACAACAGCAACACAGAAAUCUCCAACCUCACAUGCCUACAUUUCCACUAUUGACUUGGAAUAAAUUCUUACAAGUGAAAUUUAGUCAACAUAUAUAACUUUUAUGUGACAGUUGGUAAAUGUUGCUAAAUCAAUUUUCAGAAAGCAUAUGCCAAUAUUGGUUGUACAUAUUUCCUGAAAUCCUUGUCUGCACUAAGUAGCAACGUAAAAAAAGAAACUUUUCUGAGUAAUAGGUGAAAGUUUUAUCUCACUGUUUUAACUUGUACUUCUGUGGUUACCUGUGAGGUUUAACGCUUUUCAAAUGAUUGUUGGUGUUUUGCAUUUUUUUAGUGAAUAAUCUGUUCGUAUUCUUCUUUGUUUUGCAAUAUGGGCUUUAAAAAACCUAUUUCUAAUUUUAUGUGUUAAAAUUGGUAACACAUAUAGGGCAGAAAUAUGUGUUACUAGUCUGUAGUUUGGCUUUGGCUUGUGUUGAAAAGGUUUUAGAAAGUCAAACAGUUUUUUGCUUUAUGUAUCAUCAGGAACUGUGAAGAGCUGAGGUUCCACCUCCUCCCAAGCUGACAAGUGACCCUCGGAGAAGAACCGUGAAAACCUCACAACAGUGAAGUUAGUUUAAACAAGUUACAACGACAAACACAUUGUGCCAUCCUUAUGAUUUCACCUGUUACUUAGUUCACACUGAUGGGUGGCUGGUGUUUAAAUGCUUUCCAAGUUCAUUUCAUUUAUUAUACAAAUGCCUGUGAAAUACCCAGGCAGCAUCAUUGCUUCCUUCUCUAGCCUCCAAACCGAAUAUCCUUUUGCUCAAGCAUCCAGGUAAAAAAAGGGGGACCUUAGGAAUUGUGAAUUUGAAGCCAGAAGCCAUGGUUUACCUAGGAAUGGAUUUACUUGCCAAGAACUGUGACACCUUUAUAAAUAAAGUUACUCAUGUUGGCUUUUUUGCUCUUUAAA